GACUUCCUGUUGUGCCCGCGCCCCGCCGCCGCCGCCGCCCGGCGCCCCUCGCCCGCGGCCCGGCGCGGCCGCCGCCCAUGGAUUUCACCUAGUGCCGGCGGCCAUGGCCGCGCAGUGCUGCUGCCGCCAGGCGCCCGGCGCCGAGGCCGCGCCCGUCCGCCCGCCGCCCGAGCCGCCGCCCGCCCUGGACGUGGCCUCGGCCUCCAGCGCGCAGCUCUUCCGCCUCCGCCACCUGCAGCUGGGCCUGGAGCUGCGGCCCGAGGCGCGCGAGUUGGCCGGCUGCCUGGUGCUCGAGCUGUGCGCGCUGCGGCCCGCGCCCCGCGCGCUCGUGCUCGACGCGCACCCGGCUCUGCGCCUGCACUCAGCCGCCUUCCGUCGCGCCCCCGCCGCCGCCGCCGAGACGCCCUGCGCCUUCGCCUUCUCCGCCCCCGGGCCGGGGCCCGCGCCGCCGCCCCCGCUGCCCGCCUUCCCCGAGGCGCCCGGCUCCGAGCCCGCCUGCUGUCCGCUGGCCUUCAGGGUGGACCCGUUCACCGACUACGGCUCCUCGCUCACCGUCACGCUGCCGCCCGAGCUGCAGGCGCACCAGCCCUUCCAGGUCAUCCUGCGGUACACCUCGACCGACGCCCCCGCCAUCUGGUGGCUGGACCCAGAGCUGACCUAUGGCUGCGCCAAGCCCUUCGUCUUCACCCAGGGCCACUCCGUGUGCAACCGCUCCUUCUUCCCGUGCUUCGACACACCUGCCGUGAAGUGCACCUACUCUGCCGUCGUCAAGGCGCCAUCGGGGGUGCAGGUGCUGAUGAGUGCCACCCGGAGUGCAUACAUGGAGGAAGAAGGCGUCUUCCACUUCCACAUGGAGCACCCCGUGCCCGCCUACCUCGUGGCCCUGGUGGCCGGAGACCUCAAGCCGGCAGACAUCGGGCCCAGGAGCCGCGUGUGGGCCGAGCCAUGCCUCCUGCCCACGGCCACCAGCAAGCUGUCGGGCGCAGUGGAGCAGUGGCUGAGUGCAGCUGAGCGGCUGUAUGGGCCCUACAUGUGGGGCAGGUACGACAUUGUCUUCCUGCCACCCUCCUUCCCCAUCGUGGCCAUGGAGAACCCCUGCCUCACCUUCAUCAUCUCCUCCAUCCUGGAGAGCGAUGAGUUCCUGGUCAUCGAUGUCAUCCACGAGGUGGCCCACAGUUGGUUCGGCAACGCUGUCACCAACGCCACGUGGGAAGAGAUGUGGCUGAGCGAGGGCCUGGCCACCUAUGCCCAGCGCCGUAUCACCACCGAGACCUACGGUGCUGCCUUCACCUGCCUGGAGACUGCCUUCCGCCUGGACGCCCUGCACCGGCAGAUGAAGCUUCUGGGAGAGGACAGCCCGGUCAGCAAACUGCAGGUCAAGCUGGAGCCAGGAGUGAAUCCCAGCCACCUGAUGAACCUGUUCACCUACGAGAAGGGCUACUGCUUCGUGUACUACCUGUCCCAGCUCUGCGGAGACCCACAGCGCUUUGAUGACUUUCUCCGAGCCUAUGUGGAGAAGUACAAGUUCACCAGCGUGGUGGCCCAGGACCUGCUGGACUCCUUCCUGAGCUUCUUCCCGGAGCUGAAGGAGCAGAGCGUGGACUGCCGGGCAGGGCUGGAAUUCGAGCGCUGGCUCAAUGCCACAGGCCCGCCGCUGGCUGAGCCGGACCUGUCUCAGGGAUCCAGCCUGACCCGGCCCGUGGAGGCCCUUUUCCAGCUGUGGACCGCAGAACCUCUGGACCAGGCAGCUGCCUCGGCCAGCGCCAUUGACAUCUCCAAGUGGAGGACCUUCCAGACAGCACUCUUCCUGGACCGGCUCCUGGAUGGGUCCCCGCUGCCGCAGGAGGUGGUGAUGAGCCUGUCCAAGUGCUACUCCUCCCUGCUGGACUCGAUGAACGCUGAGAUCCGCAUCCGCUGGCUGCAGAUUGUGGUCCGCAACGACUACUAUCCUGACCUCCACAGGGUGCGGCGCUUCCUGGAGAGCCAGAUGUCACGCAUGUACACCAUCCCGCUGUACGAGGACCUCUGCACCGGUGCCCUCAAGUCCUUCGCGCUGGAGGUCUUCUACCAGACGCAGGGCCGGCUGCACCCCAACCUGCGCAGAGCCAUCCAGCAGAUCCUGUCCCAGGGCCUGGGCUCCAGCACAGAGCCCGCCUCAGAGCCCAGCACGGAGCUGGGCAAGGCUGAAGCAGACACAGACUCGGACGCACAGGCCCUGCUGCUUGGGGACGAGGCCCCCAGCAGUGCCAUCUCUCUCAGGGACGUCAAUGUGUCUGCCUAGCCCUGUUGGCGGGCUGACCCUCGACCUCCCAGACACCACAAUUGUGCCUUCUGUGGGCCAGGCCUGCCAUGACUGCGUCUCGGCUCUGGCCAUGAGCUCUGCCCAGGCCCACAAGCCCCUCCCCUGGGCUCUCCCAGGCAGGGAGAAUGGGGAGAGGGACCUCCUUGUGUCUGGCAGAGACCUGUGGACCUGGCCUCCCCACUCCCAGCUCUCUUGCACUGCAGGCCCUGGGGCCAGCCCGCACACACCAUGCCUCCUGUCUCAACACUGACAGCUGUGCCUAGCCCCGGAUGCCAGCACCUGCCAGGUGCCGCCCCGGGGCAAGGGCCCCAGCAGCCCUAUGGUGACCGCCACACUGUGCCUUAAUGUCUGCCGGGGGCCCAGGCUGUGCUGUCCCUGCAGCACGCCUCCUUGCAGGGAUCUGAGCCACCCUCCCCGCACAGCCCUGCACCCCGCCCCUGGGGUUGGCAGCCUCAGUUGGCCCCUGGCAGAGGAACAAGGACACAGACAUUCCCUCAGUGUGGGGGGCAGGGGACACAGGGAGAGGAUGGUUGUCCCUGGGGAGGGCCCUCUGGCCCCAGGCAACCUUAGCCCCUCAGAACAGGGAGUCCCAGGACCCAGGGAGAGUGUGGGGACAGGACAGCCUGUCUCUUGUAGCUUCCUGGGGUGGGAGGCACAGGGGCAAAGCAAUACCCCAGGGAAAGUGGGAGGUGGUGCUGGUGCUCUCUCCAGGCCCACCAUGCUGGGAGAGGCGGCCAGAGCCUGGGGCCUCCAGCCUGGGACUGCUGUGAUGGGGUAUCACGGUGAUGGUCCCAUUAAACUUCCACUCUGCAAACCUGAUCUCCUGCGCUCUUUCUCGCGACUCUUGUCCUCUGCAUCUUCCUGGCUGUGUAGGGUGGGCUGGCCUGCCGGGACUUGGGGCCUGGAGCUGGUCAGGAGCUGGGUGUGGCCCCCUCCUCUGAUACAUAAGCCCGAGAGCAGGCUCCCCGAAUCCUGCCCAGCCCCUUGGCUGGACCCCCUGGGCCUGAGUAGCCUCUGGAUGUCACAGGAAAGCCAUGUGUCACCUUCACUCUGGGCCUUCACCUGUGGCUUAAGCCAAAUCCCGGCCUCAGUGGUGAUCCUUUCCCAAGAUGGGUACAAGGUGACAGGCAUGUUUUGUUUUGGAGAACUGAGAUUUCCAUUUUCCCAGGCGAUAGGUGUCGCUGCCCUUCACAGUCCCCAAGGAUGUGGCGCCACCAUCUCAGUGCCACGCACACCUGGCCAACAUGCCGUGGCCCAGAAGCAGCACGUCUCUUCUCCCAACCCGCUGGCCAGGCCCAGUCACAGCCCCACUCCACACAUGGCAGCCAGGAAGUGGGGAGGGCAGGAGGUGCUGGGCAAAUAACCCUGAUACCAUCACUGUCCAGUCCCCAGUCACCAAAUGUCCCACUCACCCUCCUUCCUGUUCUGGAUGCCCCGCCCCUCCCCUCCCCUCCCAAGGACAUAUGAGUCCCCUCCAGUGGCGGUGGCAACUCUGGUCUAGGGUCUGGGGCCGUCUCUACAUGUGUUGCUUCAUGUACCUUCUUCACAUCAGGUCUGGGGGAGGCGCCACCCCAUCCAGAGACCUAGGAACUAGAAGACUGCCACUGCCCCUCACACCCAGGGAUAGGAUGACUGCAGUAACCCCUGUGAAAGCGGGUAUGGAGGGCACCUGGCAGCCCCUGCUGCAUGGCCAUCUAAAGUCUUGCCAGGCAGGCACAGCUAGGGCCCCUGCCUGGGAGUGGACACCCCACUCCCCCAAGUCAUGUUCUCUGUGGCCUGGGGCUCCAGCCUUGGGAGGACCCCUUUCCUGUUUCUUAACCAUGCUUGAUGGUGUCCUCAAAGGAGCCCUGCUCAGUGGCAGAACUGCUUUCUCAGCCUCUUCCCCGCCAAGGUUGUUUUCAAGUCCCAGCAGUCACAGACUUUCAUCCUGGGCUCUUCUUUCUUUUGCAAUUCAGCUCUCGAAAUGACUCUGUGGUCUGCGGGUGACUCCACUCCACGUGCCUACAGCCACGCCCACAGCGCCACCUCCGGACGCUGCUGAGCUGCGCACCUGUGCCUGACACCUGGCUUUGGGAAACUCAGCAGCAGUGCCCAGCGUCAUGACCCUGGGGGCAGGAGGGCAUCUGGAUCCAGGAUGGCACCCUCACCACAAUCUGUCUUGGCUCUGUGCCCGCCCGUGGGGUACACAGGAGGGCUCUUUCAGCCCUAAGUCCUUGUGUUCCUGACCUUUGUUCCUCUUCCACCCAGCUUGCAAGUGCAGAAUUUUUUUUUAGCUCGUCGCUUCCCUGCAGUCCCUUGUCCAAUGCAGCCUCCGGCCGAUACUCAGGCCAGUGUUGUUUCCCAACCUCUCCACUAGAUACGCACACUUAGCUCACGGUCUGCCUCAUGAGUCAUCCCAGUUGAGCUUUACCAAAUGUUUUGCCCCACCUAACAGCCUGCCCACAUUCCAAAUCCUGGCAGGUCGCACGUUUUAUUAGCACAGCACCCCUCUCCUAGCGGCCAGCUUCUCUAUUAGGCCACGUUAUGCUCCAGCCACACAACUAUGAAGCGCAGACGUCUCACACAACAAAGCUUUCUCAUGCUGCAGGCCCACCUCAGGCUGGCAGGGGAAGGGGGGAUUCUCUUCAAUGUGACCACUCUCGGACCCGUACCGAUGAACAGAGAUCUCAAAUGUUUCCAGGCACCUUGCCAGGGAUAAGAGAGCUGUUGAGGGGCUCACACUGGCAGUGGAAGUUCUAAGGGGCCUACAACCACAGGGGCUGCAACCCCACCAUAUGCACAAAAGCGGGGGCAGAUGGCAAACAGCACUAAUGACAACGACGGAGCUGAGGCCAGAAUGUGAGAGAGAUCUGCAUUUUGGGGAUUAGGGCCUAGUCAGGCAGGUAGGAGAUGAUGUUCAAAAAGGGAAAAGAAGCGUGAUGAAAGACUGGUUUCUACAGAGAUAGAUUAGAAAGCUGAAGCCUGAAAAAACAGUGAAGGAGACCCAUGCAAAUUUCUAGGCCCUGGAGGUCCAAAUAAGGUUUUCUAAGUCCCUCAGGCCAUGACAGGUUCAGUCCAGACUUGUCUCCCAGAGUGUUUCUCUGCCAUCCCUACUCUAACUGGGACUUAUUGGUGGUGUUUCUCUCCUAAGGCCAGAUGCUUUGCACAGAACAUUAGGAAACUCCAGAUGUAAAGGUAAGGCACAACUGAGAAUCACCUGCCCAGGGCAGCAACACAGUGUGAAGGAAAACAGGCCACUCAACCCAAACUUACACCUGAGACAGAGGCAACAGAAAAAUCAGAAAAGGACUUUAGAACACAUAUAAUCAAAAUCUCAGACCUAAAGACGACUUUUGAAAUAAACCAUAACAUAUGAAGAGGCACUUAUGAAACAAGAACAGGUAGUUUAUAAAAAAGAACCAGUCAGAGACCCUGGAAAUUUUUUAAAAAGCAAUUACUAAAAUAAAAAAUGAAAACUCA